GCACUCGCCUCGGCUCCCACACAGCCGCCUCUGCUCCAGCAAGGAUGUGGCUCUUCCACACUCUGCUCUGCAUAGCCAGCCUGGCCCUGCUGGCCGCUUUCAAUGUGGAUGUGGCCCGGCCCUGGCUCACGCCCAAGGGAGGUGCCCCUUUCGUGCUCAGCUCCCUUCUGCACCAAGACCCCAGCACCAACCAGACCUGGCUCCUGGUCACCAGCCCCAGAACCAAGAGGACACCAGGGCCCCUCCAUCGAUGUUCCCUUGUCCAGGAUGAAAUCCUUUGCCAUCCUGUAGAGCAUGUCCCCAUCCCCAAGGGGAGGCACCGGGGAGUGACCGUUGUCCGGAGCCACCACGGUGUUUUGAUAUGCAUUCAAGUGCUGGUCCGGCGGCCUCACAGCCUCAGCUCAGAACUCACAGGCACCUGUAGCCUCCUGGGCCCUGACCUCCGUCCCCAGGCUCAGGCCAACUUCUUCGACCUUGAAAAUCUCCUGGAUCCAGAUGCACGUGUGGACACUGGAGACUGCUACAGCAACAAAGAAGGCGGUGGAGAAGACGAUGUGAACACAGCCAGGCAGCGCCGGGCUCUGGAGAAGGAGGAGGAGGAAGACAAGGAGGAGGAGGAAGACGAGGAGGAGGAGGAAGCUGGCACCGAGAUUGCCAUCAUCCUGGAUGGCUCAGGAAGCAUUGAUCCCCCAGACUUUCAGAGAGCCAAAGACUUCAUCUCCAACAUGAUGAGGAACUUCUAUGAAAAGUGUUUUGAGUGCAACUUUGCCUUGGUGCAGUAUGGAGGAGUGAUCCAGACUGAGUUUGACCUUCGGGACAGCCAGGAUGUGAUGGCCUCCCUCGCCAGAGUCCAGAACAUCACUCAAGUGGGGAGUGUCACCAAGACUGCCUCAGCCAUGCAACACGUCUUAGACAGCAUCUUCACCUCAAGCCACGGCUCCAGGAGAAAGGCAUCCAAGGUCAUGGUGGUGCUCACCGAUGGUGGCAUAUUCGAGGACCCCCUCAACCUUACGACAGUCAUCAACUCCCCCAAAAUGCAGGGUGUUGAGCGCUUUGCCAUUGGGGUGGGAGAAGAAUUUAAGAGUGCUAGGACUGCGAGGGAACUGAACCUGAUCGCCUCAGACCCGGAUGAGACCCAUGCUUUCAAGGUGACCAACUACAUGGCGCUGGAUGGGCUGCUGAGCAAACUGCGGUACAACAUCAUCAGCAUGGAAGGCACGGUUGGAGACGCCCUUCACUACCAGCUGGCACAGAUUGGCUUCAGUGCUCAGAUCCUGGAUGAGCGGCAGGUGCUGCUCGGCGCCGUCGGGGCCUUUGACUGGUCCGGAGGGGCGUUGCUCUACGACACACGCAGCCGCCGGGGCCGCUUCCUGAACCAGACAGCGGCGGCGGCGGCAGACGCGGAGGCUGCGCAGUACAGCUACCUGGGUUACGCUGUGGCCGUGCUGCACAAGACCUGCAGCCUCUCCUACAUCGCGGGGGCUCCACGGUACAAACAUCAUGGGGCCGUGUUUGAGCUCCAGAAGGAGGGCAGAGAGGCCAGCUUCCUGCCAGUGCUGGAGGGAGAGCAGAUGGGGUCCUAUUUUGGCUCUGAGCUGUGCCCUGUGGACAUUGACAUGGAUGGAAGCACGGACUUCUUGCUGGUGGCUGCUCCAUUUUACCACGUUCAUGGAGAAGAAGGCAGAGUCUACGUGUACCGUCUCAGCGAGCAGGAUGGUUCUUUCUCCUUGGCACGCAUACUGAGUGGGCACCCCGGGUUCACCAAUGCCCGCUUUGGCUUUGCCAUGGCGGCUAUGGGGGAUCUCAGUCAGGAUAAGCUCACAGAUGUGGCCAUCGGGGCCCCCCUGGAAGGUUUUGGGGCAGAUGAUGGUGCCAGCUUCGGCAGUGUGUAUAUCUACAAUGGACACUGGGACGGCCUCUCCGCCAGCCCCUCGCAGCGGAUCAGAGCCUCCACGGUGGCCCCAGGACUCCAGUACUUCGGCAUGUCCAUGGCUGGUGGCUUUGAUAUUAGUGGCGACGGCCUUGCCGACAUCACCGUGGGCACUCUGGGCCAGGCGGUUGUGUUCCGCUCCCGGCCUGUGGUUCGCCUGAAGGUCUCCAUGGCCUUCACCCCCAGCGCACUGCCCAUCGGCUUCAACGGCGUCGUGAAUGUCCGUUUAUGUUUUGAAAUCAGCUCUGUAACCACAGCCUCUGAGUCAGGCCUCCGCGAGGCACUUCUCAACUUCACGCUGGAUGUGGAUGUGGGGAAGCAGAGGAGACGGCUGCAGUGUUCAGACGUAAGAAGCUGUCUGGGCUGCCUGAGGGAGUGGAGCAGCGGAUCCCAGCUUUGUGAGGACCUCCUGCUCAUGCCCACAGAGGGAGAGCUCUGUGAGGAGGACUGCUUCUCCAAUGCCAGUGUCAAAGUCAGCUACCAGCUCCAGACCCCUGAGGGACAGACGGACCAUCCCCAGCCCAUCCUGGACCGCUACACUGAGCCCUUUGCCAUCUUCCAGCUGCCCUAUGAGAAGGCCUGCAAGAAUAAGCUGUUUUGUGUCGCAGAAUUACAGUUGGCCACCACCGUCUCUCAGCAGGAGUUGGUGGUGGGUCUCACAAAGGAGCUGACCCUGAACAUUAACCUAACUAACUCCGGGGAAGAUUCCUACAUGACAAGCAUGGCCUUGAAUUACCCCAGAAACCUGCAGUUGAAGAGGAUGCAAAAGCCUCCCUCUCCAAACAUUCAGUGUGAUGACCCUCAGCCGGUUGCUUCUGUCCUGAUCAUGAACUGCAGGAUUGGUCACCCCGUCCUCAAGAGGUCAUCUGUGAGUCGGUUUGGACUGAUUCGCUCUUCUCACCACCCUGCAGUUGGCGUCUUCUGCAUCUUGGCUCAUGUUUCAGUCGUUUGGCAGCUAGAGGAGAAUGCCUUUCCAAACAGGACAGCAGACAUCACUGUGACUGUCACCAAUUCCAAUGAAAGACGGUCUUUGGCCAACGAGACCCACACCCUUCAAUUCAGGCAUGGCUUCGUUGCAGUUCUGUCCAAACCAUCCAUAAUGUACGUGAACACAGGCCAGGGGCUUUCUCACCACAAAGAAUUCCUCUUCCAUGUACAUGGGGAGAACCUCUUUGGAGCAGAAUACCAGUUGCAAAUUUGCGUCCCAACCAAAUUACGAGGUCUCCAGGUUGUAGCAGUGAAGAAGCUGACGAGGACUCAGGCCUCCACGGUGUGCACCUGGAGUCAGGAGCGCGCUUGUGCGUACAGUUCGGUUCAGCAUGUGGAAGAAUGGCAUUCAGUGAGCUGUGUCAUCGCUUCAGAUAAAGAAAAUGUCACCGUGGCUGCAGAGAUCUCCUGGGAUCACUCUGAGGAGUUACUAAAAGAUGUAACUGAACUGCAGAUCCUUGGUGAAAUAUCUUUCAACAAAUCUCUAUAUGAGGGACUGAAUGCAGAGAACCACAGAACUAAGAUCACUGUCGUCUUCCUGAAAGAUGAGAAGUACCAUUCUUUGCCUAUCAUCAUUAAAGGCAGCGUUGGUGGACUUCUGGUGUUGAUCGUGAUUCUGGUCAUCCUGUUCAAGUGUGGCUUUUUUAAAAGAAAAUAUCAACAACUGAACUUGGAGAGCAUCAGGAAGGCCCAGCUGAAAUCAGAGAAUCUGCUCGAAGAAGAGAAUUAGGACCUGCUAUCCACUGGGAGAGGCUAUCAGCCAGUCCUGGGACUUGGAGACCCAGCAUCCUUUGCAUUACUUUUUCCUUCAGGAUGAUCUAGAGCAGCAUGGAGCUGUUGGUAGAAUAUUAGUUUUUAACCAUACAUUGUCCCAAAAGUGUCUGUGCAUUGUGCAAAAAGUAAACUUAGGAAACAUUUGGUAUUAAAUAAAUUUACACUUUUCUUUGCA